AAAAAAAAAAAGUAAAAUUGUAAAAAAUUUUAGAUUUUUCAAGCCAUAUAGUCUCUAUUACAACUACUCAACUAUGUUGUAAUAGCUAGACAAUAUCCAUACACAAGAUAUAAAUGAGUGGACAUGGCUGUGUUUCAAUAAAACUUUACUUACACAGACAGGUGGUGGGACGGAUUUGGGCUGUGGGUCACAGUUUGCUGACCCCUGAUCUAGAAAAUGCCUUGCAGCUGUCAAAUAGCAAAGCCAACAGUAGCAACUGUUGUUAUUAACAAAGAAAAAGCUACAAUAUAUUCCUGAUAAAGCAAGUAGAUCAGUGUUGUUAGAAAAUGGGCUUUCUGUAGGUGAUAGUUAGAAGGAUGACUGUAAAUAAUGGUAAAAAAAUGCUAAGACUUCAAUGCCAAGAAAUAUCAAGCAGGGAAUGGAAAACAGAAAGCAGUUUUCCUGGAAGUACCUUACAGGAAUUCUAUGAAACCAGAGAAAUUAGAAAAUGGAAAACAGACAAGGAGUGUUUACAAUAAAUGAGGCAUAAGGCAAUGGGGGGCCUAUGUUUAGAGUAUUAAUGGUAGAAGUGCCAAAGAAAAUAAAACAGAUUCAAGGUCAUUUUUGGAAGAAAAAAAUCCAUGAGAGAUGAUACUUGAUUGGAUAUAUUCUGAGCUUCAUUGGAUGUUGCUAUGGGAAAUAAGUAAAAGAGACAGCAAGAGGCCUAUCUUAAUGCUUUUCAAUACAAACCUAAACAUUUUUACCAAAACAACUCAAGCUCUGAGAAAUAAAAUCGCCUACACUUUAAGCUAUUAGACAGGGAAACAUGUAAAUAAAGUUCCCCCAUCGCUGGUUUGCCAUAGAGCAUUUGAAUAAAUAAAGGAAGGAGUUUGGGGGUACUUUCUAGGUUCUCUGAUGGUCUGCUUAUUAGUCUUUCCCUUAGAUCAUCUUAAAGGCAAAGGUGUAACUUUGCAUCUUUGCAUCUUUGCAUCUCUUAUUACACAUAUAUGAUCACUGAGAUCUGAACAGAGUAAAAUCUUUUGAUUAGUUGUCACAGUUUGGGGGUGGCUUUGUGUAUAACAAGAAUCUUAGAAAUAACGGUGGCUUAAACAGGAGAGAACUUUGUCAGGGAAAAGUCCAAUAUAUCCAAAUUUCAGAGCGGAUGUAUUGGCUGCCUAAUUGUCUAGGCCUCAGGAUUCUGCCCUCUAUAGGGUAUGGUCUUCAUCCUUAUUUUCCCAAGAUGAAACUCUGUCCAUCAUAUCUACGCUAUUACAAGCUCGAAGGUGUAGACUGAAAGGAACAAAGGACAUGAUCCUUCCCACCUUUAAGAACAAGUCCCAGAGGUUACUUAUAUCACUUUUACUUACAUUCAUAGGCCAGAACUUGUUCACAUAACUACACCAAGCUGUAGUGAUGGCUUGGGUAUGUAGUUUUUGUUAGUAAAACCCAUGUGCCUGAUAAAAAUACUACUAAUUUAAGGAUUUCAAAUUGAUUUCCCUAAGAGAAAAGCCUAAGAUAGGGAUUCCUGUGCAAGUGAGCUAUGAAGAGAGUGCUCUCAGAAAAAAACCUGCAGGGAAGAAGUCAGGCAGAGAUGUGUUUUCAAGUCUAGCUUCAGCCUGAUCCCACAGGGAGCUGUGGUGCAUAAAUUGCAUCACAGAGUUUAAUCUCACAUUGAAGCAAGCCUGGACAUCGCAAGUAUCUCUAUCUGAGUGGUUCUUGUCAUACCAAGGUGAUUAUCAAGAAAAGGGUACAGCUAUGGGCCUUGACCAGCUAGUACCCACAGCAGCUAGAGAAUGAGUACAACAGCUGGUGAAGAAAUUCUGGGUGGGAUGUCAAAAGCAUCUGCUACACUGAAGAAGGAGGACAGAUUUUGAGGGAAAAUUAGUAGCCAUUUUUGUAAGAGCCAAAAGUAUCCCUUCACACAUACUGAGAUGACUCAAUAUCCUAUUUCUGUUUUGUACAUGGUUAGUACUCUAUCAGUAUUUGUAGAAUGAGUAAUGCAUAUUCUUGGACAACCUUCUUUUUUUUUUUUUAAUUUCCACAGCCAUCCUUUACCAUUUUUGAAAGUAUUAAGAAAUGUUAAUACUUUCAGUACCACCAUACCUACCCCCAGUACAUACACAAGCAUCCUGCCCUCAAUAGCUAUUUCCUCUACUCAGAUUCUAAGUCACACUCACAACCAAUUGUAGAAUUACCUCACUGGCAUUCUGAAGAAUUAGCUGGCAAAUUUCCUGCAUUUUCAAAUAUUUUAAGUUCCGGUUUCCAGAAAAAUUCUCCUUGCCCUGGAAAUAAUAGCCAGACAACUAUGAUUAGAAUAUAUAUAACCUGCUUAUAUUCACCUUCUUUAAAUCUUUGGUGAAGAAUAGGUAUGGCUUUUCUCAUCGGUUUGCUCUGGCCUAGAUUUAUGUUGGUUUUACAGUGACAUUUCUGACUUUCAGGCAAGUAUCCAUUGAGUAACUGUUUUAUUAUACAAAAUCUGAGGUUAUAAAAUAAAGACUUAAAUGAGCAUUUCACUGAUUUCAUUAUAUCUCACAAUUAUAGAUCUGGAUCUAUCAAUUUUUUCUCAUGAAGGUCCCAAAAGACUGUUCUAUAAGAGCCGUGAUUAUGGAGUGAAUGAGUCAAAUUUGAAGUCUGGUCCAAUGGUUUCAGGAAAAUGUUUUAUAUUGUUCUAAAGCCAAAAAAUAAAGAAAGAAUAAAGCAUCAUUUCAAAGCACUAUCACACCAGGUUGGAUUAGUUAGGCUUCAUAUUACAGAAAAGCAGCUUAAGUAAGAUAGUUUAGUUUCUCACGUAAAGUAGUUAUAAGGUAGGCAUUCCUGGACUUUUAUGAUAAUUUCAACGUUUUGCAUGACUUAGGCUCUAAAGCUUUAUGCUUUGCCAUUCUCAGCAUGUGGCUUCCAUUCCCAAUGUCACUACGUGCUCCUAAUACAACUGAAGAACUGAAUUUUUAAUGUUAUUUAAUUUUAAAUAGCCACAUGUGGAUCUUAGUCUUUGUUUUCAAAUAGUCAUUACAAGCUGUUUGUGGCUACUGUUUUAGAAUAGAAACUCUUCUGGAUAGCUCUUAUUUAGCCUGGAAUCAUGUAAUGUAAACAUGGAAAAGAUUUUAGAUUUCACUGUAGGGGUUGCUUAGUUUUACAGAUAAACAAUGGAGGAAGUCCAAAGAAGUAUUGGCUUUCUAGAAAUUCAAAACUAAUGUUUAGAAAUACUGAAAAUCGAGCUGGAUCUUUUGAUUUCUUAAUCAGUGCACUCAUAAAAAAUAAUUUAUUAAAAAUAUUUUGUAAUUGAAUUUGUUGAUUAUUCAGGUAGAUCUUCCUUUAUUUACUUAAAAAAGUAAGAUUUUAAUACAAUUAUUUUUUUCAAUCCAUUCAUUUCCAAUGGCUAAUUUAUUUGAAGAAUGAUUGCAGCAAUCUGACAACAAAGUUUUACCCCAUCUACUCUAGAUAUUGAGGCUUAGGCUGUGUUUCUAUUCUUGACUCUAUAAGCCAAUCCAUUAAAUGAUAAGCUAACAAUUAAUUUACAUUAAAACAAGACUACUAUUUCUGUUACUGUAGAAGUUUUAGAAUUAGUUGCAUGUAAGUUAAUGUGAUUAAAUUGGCUAGGAAUAUUUGAUACUGUAUCUAUUUAAUUUAUUCUUUUAGAUUAUUAAGUAUCUAUUCUAUGCAAGCCAUUAGGCCAGCUGUUGGGAGCACAGCAGUGAAUUAAACCACAGUAGAAUUAAGCUAGAAUAGAACAUGUCUCUUCUGGAAGUUUAUUCUAGAAAAGAGCCUUUGAAACAGUAAUUACUUGGAUCCUAACUUUUAUGAAGAGAAAGAACAAGGUGCCUUAAGAUCAGGCAACAGGCUGGCUUAGCCCACUUGGUAAAUAGUCUCUCCCUCAAAGGCUCAACCUCUUCAAACUGAAAUCUGACUACUUCUGAGGUUGCACAAAAGUUCCACAGACUGUUCCGAAAAAAAUAAUUUGAAGGAAAUUCAUCUCCAGAACCUCAACUUUCACAUGUACUCUUGUCUAAAAUUGCCUGAAAUCUCAGAAUAGCAUUUCCUCCACCUUACAAAAGAAAGGCACACCUUUCUUCCUUCCCAAAUUGUAGCAUGAUGCAUUGCCCCAGAACUUAGGGUGCCAAACAAAGGGAUAGUCUAAAAUAUUACUUUGAAAACUCAAGGCCCCUUAAACUCAGAGAUCUUCUCCUGCCUGUGUUUCAGGAAUUUUUGAUAACUUCAGUGCUUAAUCAAAGUUGGUAUAUUCCUAAUUCAGAACAGCCAAAGCCUUAUAUAGUAGUGAUACUGAAUUGUGUCAGUGUAAUUGGAAUGUUUUAUAGGACUAUCAUUUUUUCAAGAUGCAUUUGAUAAAACUCAGGAACACACUUUACUUGUGAUGGUUAAUACUGAGUGUCAACUUGAUUGGAUUGAAGGAUGCAAAGUAUUGAUCCUGGGUGUAUCUGUGAGGGUGUUGCCAAAGGAGAUUAACAUUUGAGUCAGUGAGCUAGGAAAGGCAGACCCACCCUUAAUCUGGGUGGGCACCAUCUAUUCAGCUGCCAGCACAGCUAGAAUAUAAAGCAGGCAGAAAAAAAAAAACACGUGAAAGGACUAGACUGGCCUAGCCUCCCAGCCUACAUCUUUCUCCCAUGCUGGACCCUUCCUGCCCUCAAAUAUUGGACUCCAAGCUCUUCAGUUUUGGGACUCGGGCUGGCUCUCCUUGCUCCUCAGCUUGCAGACAGCCUAUUAAGGGACCUUGUGAUCAUGUGAAUUAAUACUUAAUAAAUUCCCAUAUAUAUGUCCUAUUAGUUCUGUCCCUCUAGAGAACCCUGACCAAUACAUUUGUUUUCUUUCAUAUUUGAUGUGCAUUGUCCAAAAAUAACACAUGGAAAGCCUAUUUCAUUAAAUCAUGUACUAUGUAUUCCACUUAGUUAAUUCUCAUCAUAUUCCAUUUAUACAAUAUAUAGUAUUUUCUCUCUCCUAUUAACAAAUAACUAAAAUUAUUUAAACAUACAAAAAUAGAUGUCACCUUUAAAUAAUAGGUUUUUAUAAGUCAUUUAAGGUAAAUGUGACACAAAAAAGCUUGGAAACCCCUUUUCAGGGUUUCUCAAAUUAUAAUCGUAUGUCUAAUUAGAUUAAAAAAGGUCACCAAGGUGCUAGUGAAUAAAACAAACAAACAGAUUCCUAGAUCCUACCACUUACUGUUGAAUCAGAAUUUCUGGGGAAACAAGGAUCAGAAAUCUGAUGGAUCAGCAUGCAUACAGAUGAUUCUUAUCCACAUUAAGUUUGUGAAUUUAUAUUCAAGUGAUAACGGUUACUAUGGUUUGGAUGUUUGUUUCCCCAAACCUCAUGUUGAAAUUUGAUCCCAGAGUUGGAGGUCAGGUGUUACUAAUGGGAGUUUGAGUAAUGCGGGUGUGUCCUUCAUGAAAAGAUUAAUAGCCUACUUCAGCAGUGAAUGAGUUCUUGCUUAGUUUCCAGGAGAGCUGGUGCUUUAAAAGAGCCUGGCACAUCCACCUUUUUUCUCUUAUUUCUGCUCUCAUCAUGUGAUCUCUGCUCUCUUUUGCCUUCCACUAUAAGUGGAAGCAGCCUGAGUUCCUCAACAAAAGCAGAUACUGGUGCCAUGCUUUUCGUACAGCCUUCAAAACUGUAAACUAAAUAAGCAUCGCUUCUUUACAAACUAGCUAACCUCAAGUAGUUCUUUAUAGCGACACAAAAAAUGGACUAAGACAAUGAUCCUUUUAAGAGAGUUCUAUCCCAUACUAAUUCAAAGUCAACAUGGUGUUUCAUAUAAUCUUGUUGUAAUAGUCUCUUGGUGGUGGACAUCCGGCACCUAACACAGUGCCCAGCACAUGUUGGAGUGUCAAGAAUUAAUGAUUGAAAGUGAAUGGAAAAAAGGUAUAUAUCUCCUCCCAAAACAUCAGGAGAUUGAAUAUAAAGGACACAUCUUCCUUCUAUAAUGUGACAGAUGCACUCUAUAGUUACUGUUUGAGAGUUUUUUUAGUGCAAACUAUUUACCUCUUAGGCUAAAUUUAAUUUACAAAUGGAAUCAUUAGUAGUGAAGAUAUAGCAGGGUGCCUUCCAGAUUCCUCUGCUGUGAUCUUCAAAUGAAUAAGCACUGCAGAUUAGUCAACCUUCUGAAAAGUUCUUAAUUAAGGAAACCAAUACUGUGCAGAAUAACAGCCUGUGUGUUAACCUUGUUGACACAGUGUAGAAAUCUCAUGUAGAUAGCUAGUACAAAAGAAUAAAAAUGUUGUUCUAGUUUCUAAAGUGGCGUUUCCAAGGAAUUAUACUUCUAAUGAAAAUUGCUGCUGUGGAUGUCUGUUCAAAGGCUUUGGCUUACAAAGUAAAGAUUUGAAAAUAUCAAACUUGCUUAAUCUCUGAAUGUUGUUUUCAUUCAUUAGGUGAAUAUGACAGCUCUCUCUUUACCCUAAUCGCCCCCCCUGGAGGAAAUAACAUUUUUGUUUGUCUAAACAGUACUUAAUGACUACUCUAAAAUUAGAGUUUAAGAUCUUUAACUCUAGAGUGCAAAGCUCUACGUCCUUGACUCUGACGUUUAUCAUGAAUAUUAAUUUCUGAUCUUAAAGUCAAGCCAUGAAAUUUUUAUAUAUUAUCAUACAUUUCCCUUGACAGUUUUUGUAAUUGCCGUAAUUUCCUCAUCAGCAAGAGUUGUUUGUGGCUCUCCUGGUCUGAGGAGGCUAUAAAUUUGGCAGCUUUGAAUUCCCUCUUUUGUUUGAAUGUGGAACCAUCGACUUGUUUACUCUGAACAUUAACUAGAUCUCAGAUCUUAAAAGAACUAUAGUUUUUAUUGGUGCCUUUACAUGACAAAAGACUCAAUAUAUUUGUUGCCAUUACAUGUUUUCAUUGUUACCUUUGGAUUGACUUUCUUGUUAGGGGAGAUUUAUGUCCAUCUUCAGAUACUUUUCCUGCUACUCACAUAAAAAUGUUAUUUUCUGCCACAUAGCUACCAUUUUCUUUAAAAUUGAUUUAUUAGUAGUGUUUGAUUAUCGAAUACCAGACUGUAUAUAUUCACAUUGUGUAUAAGUAUCCAACAUGAAAAUUAUUUAGACAAUAUUCAUGGACAUGUAUACAUAAACACACAUACUUUUUAAUAUAUGUAAUUCAACUGAAAUGUUAUCUUCCGUUUGUACUUUCAACAAAGAUUUAUCGAACAUCUACUACACAUCAGGCCUGGAUUUUUUUCUGCACACAGGAAUAAAAAUAGACAAGACACAAAUUGGCCUGAAGAUGCCACAGUCAACCAGGCAAACAGACAGACUCAUAAAAAAUUAUCUGUAUCACUGUACGGCAAAUGCUGUUAAAAAUAUGGUGACAAAGAGCUGUUGCAACCAGAGAGACUCAGGGAUGGAUACACAGAAGACAGGUCUCUGAGGCUACACGAGAUAGAUCUUUCUUCCCAGAGAAAUUGAAAGGGCAUGUUAUUUUACACAGUAGGAGUGGCCAGACAUGGUGAUUUAGUAAAAGAGCUUCAGAAGGGAAAAGCAACAGAUACACGUGGCUGGAGUGAAAAGUGCAAAGUGGUGCGUGGGAAAGAAACAGAAGCUAGAAAGUUAACUUUUGGAUAGAUUUGGGAAGUACCCAAGAAUAGAAUCUCAGGUUCAGGUGUUUGACUUUUUUUUUCUUAGGACCUGAAGACAGUGAUCCAGGAUGGCCUAAAUGUCGCAGAGAAAAUUAUUCUAUAUAUUCAGUCAUUCAGACAAUUAUCUAAUGAAUUCUUUAUGAGAGUUGUUUUUGGCCAGGUGAUGAACAAGAGUCAAAGUCUCUGUUCUUAGGAAUCUUAUAGUCUUUCAAGAGAGAAAGUUAAGUCACUCAACGUUUAAUGUCUGAUAUGACAGAGGUUACAACAGAGAAAAGAACAGAGUGUAAUGGGCACAUAGAUGUGAUGUGUAAUUCAGAAUAAAAAUCAGGUAAGGCUUCUUGGAGAUUUAAAUAUUGAGUUCUGAUACAGAAGUAAAACUUACCUGGAUGAAAUAAGGAGAUGAAAAAGGAGAUUUGGAGGAGAUCCUAGGUGGUAAGAUAGUAUAUGGCUACAGUCAUUAUAUAUUCUUCUAAUUGUCCACGACUAUAGUAAAGUUCCCAUGACUUGGGUCAUUUUUAGAGAAGUUGGAAAGGAUCAGUUCAUGGUCUUGGGGUACAAAACGGGAGAGCUGAAACUUUACACAAAAAGGUUCAGGGAGACAAUGAAAAACUUUAAUCAGAUGGAUGACAAAAAUUGGAUUUGAGUUUUGGGGCGGUCAUUUAGCAGCAGUGUGUGGGGAUGUUGAAUGGAGGGCUUGGAGAGUAGCAUCUAACUACAGGGUUGUCUUAGAUUGGACUCCUCUAGAAACAAACCGCAAGGAAACAUCACUAGAGGAAUGGGGAAGUAAGAUGUAGCAGAGAAGGGAAGCCAGUAAAGUAUGCAUUAUAAAGCUGUUUUAUCCCUUUUGGCAACUGGAAAUUAGGUUUACUGGAAAACUCUGUGAGACAAUGUAGACAUACUCUCAGAGUUAUACCCGAAGGGAGAGGAAACUGGGUUGUUUUUCUACCAGCUCCCUACCUGUUCCUGAUUGAGGGUUUCUUCUACUAGGAAUCUUAGUUCUCUAGCAUUUCUGGCUUGCCCUUCAUGAAGACCAAGGUUGGUCUCAGGGCCAGACAAAAGCCAUCAGACUGAGGGUGUCACGUAUUUGUAAGAAGCAGCCUUCAUACGGUAGACGUUUGGGUGGGGCACUGACAUAAUCAGCUAAAGAACUAACAAGAUGGGAGGUGUUGAGGGUCUGGACUUAGGCCAUGAUAGUGGUAAUCCGGGGAAGUUUGGGAGUGCUACUAGGCCAUUGUUUUAAUAAGAUUUGGCCAUGCAUUAAAUGUUAGGGGUAAAUUAUGAAUGAUGACUUUCCAGAGAGUAGACAGAUGUUGAUGAUGUAAAAUGUGUGUGUUUAACAACGUAAAGGUUUUAGUAUAAAUAUGAAACCUAUAUUAAAGUCUCUUUAUAAUUGUAUCUAUUUUAGAAAAGUAUUAUAAUACAGCAGUAUAAAAACUCUCUAACCAGAAGACCUAGAGUACUUCCUAGAUCCAGAUUUCUAACAGCAUGAAUCUUGGAUGAUACUCUUAAUCUCUCAGAGCGUCUCAUGAAAAAAAUGGAAGUAAACAUGAAAGAAGCUUUGCAUAUGUUACGUAAACCAAAGUGUCAGUAAGCCUUGUACAAAAUUUUAACUUUUAAAUAGAAAUUACAUAAAGUAUUUGGGCCCUAGGACCUACCAAGUCGAUUAUUAUUAAUGAAUGAGUAAAUCUAGUCAAUCAAAGACCUUUCAUUUUUCCCACACCUAUAUUUGAACAGAUGCCAGUUAGUGAGCAUCUUUGUUUGUUAAUAUCUGUACUUCAUACUUAAUGGACUAAUUUUUUCUCUAUCAAAAAAGCUGCCUUUGUUAAAACAUUUCAAUCAACUAAAUUACUUAACUCUAAUGCCUAUUUUGAGGGAAAAAUAUACUUAGAGGGAGAAUUAAAUGUGUAAUUUUAUUUCUGCCUCAUUAAACCUCCUCUGUGUCUAGGCCAACAAGAGUUUCCUCCUCCUCCACCGGCACACACUUAUUGGACGCUUCAUUGUGAGAAAAUCCUCAGGUCGCUGGAACUUGGUAAAACUCCACUUACUGUAUGAAAGUAUCCAUCUCACUGACAGUGGGUGAAAAUGACACUGGACUCUGCUAUAAUUCCAAGAUGAAGUAUUUUGAAAAAGCUGAACUUAGCAAAAGCAAGGAAAUUUCAUGCCGUGACAUAGAGGAUUUUCUACUGCCAACCAGAGAACCUGAAAUCCUUUGGUACAAGGAAUGCAGGACAAAAACAUGGAGGCCAAGUAUUGUAUUCAAAAGAGAUACUCUGCUUAUAAGAGAAGUCAGAGAAGAUGACAUUGGAAAUUAUACCUGUGAAUUAAAAUAUGGAGGCUUUGUUGUGAGAAGAACUACUGAAUUAACUGUUACAGCCCCUCUGACUGAUAAGCCACCCAAGCUUUUGUAUCCUAUGGAAAGUAAACUGACAAUUCAGGAGACCCAGCUGGGUGACUCUGCUAAUCUAACCUGCAGAGCUUUCUUUGGGUACAGCGGAGAUGUCAGUCCUUUAAUUUACUGGAUGAAAGGAGAAAAAUUUAUUGAAGAUCUGGAUGAAAAUCGAGUUUGGGAAAGUGACAUUAGAAUUCUUAAGGAGCAUCUUGGGGAACAGGAAGUUUCCAUCUCAUUAAUUGUGGACUCUGUGGAAGAAGGUGACUUGGGAAAUUACUCCUGUUAUGUUGAAAAUGGAAAUGGACGUCGACACGCCAGCGUUCUCCUUCAUAAACGAGAGCUAAUGUACACAGUGGAACUUGCUGGAGGCCUUGGUGCUAUACUCUUGCUGCUUGUAUGUUUGGUGACCAUCUACAAGUGUUACAAGAUAGAAAUCAUGCUCUUCUACAGGAAUCAUUUUGGAGCUGAAGAGCUCGAUGGAGACAAUAAAGAUUAUGAUGCAUACUUAUCAUACACCAAAGUGGAUCCUGACCAGUGGAAUCAAGAGACUGGGGAAGAAGAACGUUUUGCCCUUGAAAUCCUACCUGAUAUGCUUGAAAAGCAUUAUGGAUAUAAGUUGUUUAUACCAGAUAGAGAUUUAAUCCCAACUGGAACAUACAUUGAAGAUGUGGCAAGAUGUGUAGAUCAAAGCAAGCGGCUGAUUAUUGUCAUGACCCCAAAUUACGUAGUUAGAAGGGGCUGGAGCAUCUUUGAGCUGGAAACCAGACUUCGAAAUAUGCUUGUGACUGGAGAAAUUAAAGUGAUUCUAAUUGAAUGCAGUGAACUGAGAGGAAUUAUGAACUACCAGGAGGUGGAGGCCCUGAAGCACACCAUCAAGCUCCUGACGGUCAUUAAAUGGCAUGGACCAAAAUGCAACAAGUUGAACUCCAAGUUCUGGAAACGUUUACAGUAUGAAAUGCCUUUUAAGAGGAUAGAACCCAUUACACAUGAGCAGGCUUUAGAUGUCAGUGAGCAAGGGCCUUUUGGGGAGCUGCAGACUGUCUCGGCCAUUUCCAUGGCCGCGGCCACCUCCACAGCUCUAGCCACUGCCCAUCCAGAUCUCCGUUCUACCUUUCACAACACGUACCAUUCACAAAUGCGUCAGAAACACUACUACCGAAGCUAUGAGUACGACGUACCUCCUACCGGCACCCUGCCUCUUACCUCCAUAGGCAAUCAGCAUACCUACUGUAACAUCCCUAUGACACUCAUCAACGGGCAGCGGCCACAGACAAAAUCGAGCAGGGAGCAGAAUCCAGAUGAGGCCCACACAAACAGUGCCAUCCUGCCGCUGUUGCCAAGGGAGACCAGUAUAUCCAGUGUGAUAUGGUGACAGAAAAGCAAGGGACAUCCCGUCCCUGGGAGGUUGAGUGGAAUCUGCAGUCCAGUGCCUGGAACUAAAUCCUCGACUGCUGCUGUUAAAAAACAUGCAUUAGAAUCUCUAGAACACGAGGAAAAACAGGGUCUUGUACAUAUGUUUUUUGGAAUUUCUUUGUAGCAUCAGUGUCCUCCUGUUUUACCAUGUCUUUUACCAUUACAUUUUUUGACUUUGUUUUAUAUGUCGUUGGAAUUUGUAAAUUUACAUUUUUUUUAAAGAAGAGACUGAUGUGUAGAUAGAAAACCCUUUUUUUGCUUCAUUAGUUUAGUUUUAGAAUGGGUUUUUAUUUUAUUUCCUUUUUUAAAAUUUUACUUUGCUUUUAACAUUUCCUUGGGGUGCUUGGACAAAUCUAUCCGAUGGGACAAGGAGCACCGGAUUCUUUCUCGGGUUCUGCCUAGCAUCAACUGGGCCACGUCGGCCUUCAGAGAACAGUGCAACAAAUGCCAGCAUUGCCAUUCGGGGGAAAAAAAAAAAAAAAAAAAAAAGAUGAGAAGAACACUUGUUCAUAGGAGGGCCCCACCAGUCAGAGCCCUGAAUCUCUUCCUUGUCCCACCUCAUUCCCCACCUCUACCUUUCUAAUGGCGGCAUGAUGUGUAAACUCUGUGCAGGGGUGGGGGCGGGUCUAACUGUCUUAACAUUCAAGUCACUGCUCUUCAGAAUACACUCUAGACCCAAAGGUGUGCUAAUCACUUCACAGUGACCACUACAGAGUACUAAGAAGAGAAGAUCAAGGGCAUGAAAUUGGGGAAGAGUGUUAUUUCCGUUUUUUAAAUGAGUUGAUGUACCCUUAUAUAUAUAUACAUAUAUAUAUAAAUAUAAAUAUAUAUAAAAACAACAAAACAAAACAAAAAAA